GGAGUCUGCGCUCUGGUUCGGGCUGCGGCUGCGGCUGCGGCUGCGGCUGCUACUGCUACGCUCCUAGCUUGAGGGAAAGAGGCCGAGGCCUGGGCCAAGCCCGGAGCCGCCGCUCGCCGGAGCCUCCUGGAGCCUCCGCGCCGGCUCAGCCUGGGGGCGGGCUCCGGUCCGGCCCGCCGCCGCACCCAGGACGGAGGCUGCAUGCCCGAGGACCAGGCCGGCGCAGCCAUGGAGGAGGCGUCUCCCUAUUCCUUACUUGAUAUCUGCUUGAAUUUCUUGACUACUCACCUUGAGAAGUUCUGUUCAGCCAGACAAGAUGGAACAUUGUGUCUGCAGGAACCUGGAGUAUUCCCACAGGAGGUGGCUGAUCGACUGCUUCGGACCAUGGCUUUUCAUGGUCUAUUGAAUGAUGGAACUGUGGGUAUUUUUAGGGGCAACCAGAUGCGCUUAAAGCGAGCCUGCAUUCGCAAAGCAAAGAUCUCUGCUGUUGCUUUCCGGAAAGCUUUCUGCCACCACAAGUUAGUGGAACUUGAUGCCACAGGUGUGAAUGCUGAUAUCACGAUUACAGACAUUAUCAGUGGGCUUGGCAGUAACAAAUGGAUCCAGCAGAAUCUCCAGUGCCUGGUGCUGAAUUCAUUAACUCUCUCCCUCGAGGAUCCUUACGAGCGCUGCUUCAGCCGGCUUUCUGGCCUUCGAGCUUUAAGCAUCACGAAUGUUCUCUUUUACAAUGAAGACCUGGCUGAAGUUGCCUCAUUGCCAAGAUUAGAGAGCUUGGAUAUUUCUAACACCUCAAUCACAGACAUCACUGCUCUACUGGCCUGCAAAGACCGACUCAAGUCUCUAACCAUGCACCACUUGAAAUGUUUAAAAAUGACAACUACCCAGAUACUGGAUGUAGUUCGGGAACUCAAACAUCUGAAUCAUCUUGAUAUCUCAGAUGAUAAACAGUUUACAUCAGACAUAGCUCUUCGCUUACUAGAACAAAAAGACAUCCUACCUAACCUUGUUUCUCUGGAUGUUUCUGGGAGAAAGCACGUGACAGAUAAAGCCGUUGAAGCCUUUAUACAACAACGUCCAAGCAUGCAAUUUGUAGGUUUGCUGGCUACUGAUGCUGGUUACUCUGAAUUCCUCACAGGCGAAGGACAUUUGAAGGUGUCUGGGGAAGCCAAUGAAACUCAGAUUGCAGAAGCACUGAAGCGUUACAGUGAACGGGCAUUCUUUGUUCGGGAAGCUCUAUUUCAUCUUUUUAGUCUGACUCAUGUGAUGGAAAAAACAAAGCCAGAAAUUUUAAAGCUUGUGGUUACUGGGAUGAGAAACCACCCUAUGAAUUUGCCAGUGCAACUGGCUGCAAGCGCCUGUGUAUUUAACUUAACCAAGCAGGAUCUUGCUGCAGGGAUGCCUGUCCGACUCCUGGCUGAUGUGACCCAUUUGCUGCUCAAAGCCAUGGAACAUUUUCCCAAUCACCAGCAGUUACAGAAGAAUUGCCUCCUUUCACUUUGCAGUGACCGGAUCCUUCAAGAUGUUCCAUUUAACAGGUUUGAAGCAGCCAAGCUUGUCAUGCAGUGGCUUUGCAACCAUGAGGAUCAAAACAUGCAAAGGAUGGCAGUUGCUAUCAUUUCUAUCCUGGCUGCCAAGCUUUCUACAGAACAAACUGCACAGCUUGGUACUGAGCUCUUCAUUGUCAGGCAACUUCUUCAAAUAGUGAAGCAGAAAACCAAUCAAAAUUCAGUGGACACUACAUUGAAAUUUACUUUGAGUGCACUUUGGAACCUCACAGAUGAAUCUCCAACCACUUGUAGACACUUUAUUGAAAACCAAGGGUUAGAACUCUUCAUGAGGGUUCUAGAGUCUUUCCCAACUGAGUCAUCCAUUCAGCAGAAAGUUCUAGGACUUUUGAACAAUAUAGCUGAAGUACAAGAAUUACAUUCUGAAUUAAUGUGGAAAGAUUUUAUAGACCACAUCAGUAGUCUCCUACACAGUGUGGAAGUGGAAGUCAGUUACUUUGCAGCUGGAAUUAUUGCCCAUUUAAUAUCCAGAGGUGAACAAGCUUGGACAUUGAGUCGUAGCCAGAGGAAUUCUCUGCUGGAUGAUUUGCAUUCAGCUAUUUUGAAAUGGCCAACUCCAGAGUGUGAGAUGGUAGCAUACAGGUCCUUUAAUCCAUUUUUCCCAUUACUUGGCUGUUUCACAACACCAGGAGUUCAGCUAUGGGCAGUUUGGGCCAUGCAACAUGUCUGCAGCAAGAAUCCUUCAAGGUAUUGCAGCAUGCUGAUUGAAGAAGGAGGAUUGCAGCAUUUAUACAACAUCAAAGAUCAUGAACAUACUGAUCCCCAUGUCCAACAGAUUGCUGUGGCCAUUCUGGAUAGCUUAGAAAAACACAUUGUGCGCCAUGGGAGGCCACCUCCCUGUAAAAAACAGCCCCAAGCCAGACUAAAUUGAUAGCCAUAAGUAUUGGAUAGUUGAAUCACAGGAAUCCUUUUUGUGAUUGGUCCAUUUGGAAUAUCUUACCCUCCCUGAUGUUUUGGGGGUUUCUAUGACAAGAGUCAUAAAAUCAGUUUGGGAUUGAUAAUGUGUAGUACUGCCCAUGUGAACAGUCUCUAAUUUGUCUUGUGAUUUUAAACUUAUGAGUCAAGAAGGGUCUCUUCCUUUAUCAUUGCCUUUUAGGAAAUUUUCCACAUCUUUCAGUGUUUGAACUUACUUGUGCUUGAGAUUCUACAGUUUUAUGGUAAAGUUUGCACGAACCCUUAGGCCAGACUUUUCUGAUCUCAGAGUCCCUUCCAAUCAAUUUGCAGCUUCACAUAAGCUGUUGACCUGAUUUCUGACACUGCUUCAGUUGUAAAUUUUAUACUGCUUCUGUAUAAAAUGCCUUUCUUCUCUAUCUGUGUAUAUUUUAUAAGAUGUCCUUCUUAGUGUGAAAGAAGGGAAAUGUGGAUCAUCUUGUGGAAGCUAAUCACUGGCAGGAGCCUGGAUGGCUGGCGGAAAGAUAUAUGAGAAAGAAAAAUUAUGAAGGUAGAACAGAGUGUAGGAACUGGGAAUUGGUUUCAUGGUAUAGGUUUUAAAAUGAGACAGGCUACCCUUCGGGAGUCCACCUCUCUUGAGGCGGUGAGCAGAAGCUUGUCCUCCAUAUUUAUACCUAGAAGUGUGGACUGCUGGUUCCUGCACAGACUGCCGGUUAUUCACUAGGAAUAUUUCCCCAAGCACCACAGUAUAAAAUACUACAGCACUCUGUGUUAAAGACUAACUGUCUACAUCUCCAUAUGUUGUAGUGUUGUGAAAAUGUGAUUUUAAAAAAUUAUCGCCAGUUAAAACUGGCUAUUCUUUUCCUCUAUUUCAAAGUCAUUUUUGUUCAGUGGAAUAGAGACAGCAACAUGGUGUUAACCUCUCAAUUAAAAUACAAUUGACACCAGUAAAUUUUGCCAUAAAAAGUUAAAAUCUCUUGUUCAAAAUAUGUGUAUCUUCUUAAUGUGUUCAUGUUAGAGAAAGUGUCCCCAUCUCACUGCCAAAAAUGAAAGAAAAUAAUUAAACUCUUUAAAUGAUUAAAUGUAAUGAUUCUACUCGCAGUGCAUAACAGCACAUAUUUUUGACAGAUUAUUUUUUAGGCAAUUACCUUUCCUUAAGGUAUCUGAUACAGUAUAGUAAAGAAUCACUUAUAUCAGUAAUAGCACUUGAGAGAUAGCAAGUCACCAAGAAACUUAAUUUUCAUUUAAAAUUUUAUUUUGUGAAUAAGGUCAAUCUACAAUCCCAGAUAACUACAUUUUUUUUCAUAGAUGGCCAGUGUUUUCAACAGAGAUUUAAAAUGGAAUAUUAAAAUUAUAGUGAUUAUUCAGAAGCAUUUUAAUUUAGAAAGGAGCUGGUUUGUUAGUUCACUGAUGACAUUUUUUGACAAACAUUUUAUACCAUUAUCACAAUAAUCAGACUUGAAUUUUUUUUGGAGUUCCUUCAUGUGAAUGAAAACUGAGUUAAAAGAAAGUAGGCAUUUAGGUCUGGAUGCAGUGGCUCAUGCUUGUAAUCCCAGCACUUUGGGAAGCUGAAGCAGGAGGAUUGCUUGAGCCCAGAAGUUCAAGACUAGCCUGGGCAACAUAGUGAGACUCGGUCUCUACCAAAAAAAAAAAUUUUUUUUUUUUAAAUUAGCUGGGUGUGGUGGCACCUGGGAAACAGAGCGAGACGCUGACUCAAAUAAAUAUCUAAAUAGAUAUUUAGAAUCACUGAAAACCAUAUUAAAUGCUGGGUUAAUGCUGACUUAAUUGGCUUAAGGAAUUUUUAUAGGCGUAAGAUAAAUUUUCACAGACUAAGUUUAUUUCAGACAAAAUAGAGAAUUCUUUUAAAAGUUUUUUUUUUUUUUUUCCUUUUUCGAAUGUUAAUGUCUAAGACAAAGUUCAGAAAACGAGAUGGCCUGUGGUAGUUUGGAAAUUGCUAGAUAUGUUGACCGUUUCCAGGUCUUUUAUCUAGUGUAGUUAAGGGAAAGCCUAUUUAAGAAGUUUGGCUUCAAGUUUCUGUUUUAUAAGACAAAAGUGCAUAUUUCUUUACAGGCUAAUGCUAGGUUUUUGUCUUUACAAAUUAUUUUCAGAAAUGGCUAAAAGUGUACAGAAAACAGUAAAUCCCUUCUUUACUCAGAAUAACUUCUUAAUAGUUGAAGCAUCCAAAAUAUGUAAAAGCAAGGGUGGGCGUAGUGGCUCUUGCCUGUAAUCCCAGCAUUCUGGGAGGCCGAGGCGGGCAGAUCACUUGAGAUCAGGAGUUCGAGACCACCCUGGCCAACGUGGUGAAACCCCGUCUCUACUAAAAAUACAAAAACUAGCUGGGCAUGGUGGCUUUUUUGCACGCCUAUAGUCCCAGCUACUCGGGAGGCUGAGGCACGAGAAUCACUUGAACCCAGGAAGUGGAGGUUGCAGUGAGCUAAGAUCGUGCCACUGCACUCCAGCCUGGACAACGGAGUGAGACUCUGGGGAAAAAAAAAAUUAAACUUCCUACUUUUUUUCUUUUUGUAGAGACAGAGUUUCACUCUGUCGCCCAAGCUGGAGUGCAGUGGCACAAUCAUACCUCACUGCAGCCUCUUGGGCUUAUGUGAUCUUACCCCCUCAGCCUCUGGAGUAGCUGGAACUACAGGCUAAAUUUCCUACUUUGUAAACAUCAGUAGUGGCCAGAUACUUCUGAGUCUUAAAAGCAUAAUAGGCCGGGCGCGGUGGCUCACGCCUGUAAUCCCAGCACUUUGGGAGGCCGAGGUGGGUGGAUCACAAGGUCAGGAGUUCAAGACCAGCCUGGCCCAAAUGGUGAAACCCUGUCUCUACUAAAUAUACAAAAAUUAGCUGGGUGUGGUGGCGGGCACCUGUAAUCCCAGCUACUCAGGAGGCUGAGGCAGGAGAAUCGCUUGAACCUGGGAGGUGGAGGUUGUGGUGAGCCAAUAUCAUGCCACUGCACUCCAGCCUGGGUGACAGAGUAAGACUCCGUCUCAAAAAAAAAAAAAGCAUAAUAAUUUAUUACAUCCCAAAUAUAUAAAAAUUUGAGUGCCUUUGCAGUUGGGAUGGUUCCUAAAAUUGCGUAUAGAAUUAAGGCACAGAAUUGUGUGUAAGGUCCUGAAUCUGGCUAAAAUACAGUGGAUGUAUGUAUUGGAAUUAUGAGGCAUAAGUAGCCAGUAUCUAUAGUUAGAAUCUACAAGGCCUCCUUUUUGCACCUGUAGACUAGAAUAUAACUGUUAUUGGUGCCUUUGAGUGUUAUCUCUCAGUGGCUAGAGGUGCUGUUUCAAGCACAAUUUAGACUAGGGUUGAACCACUCAUUGUUCAAAUCAUUGGUGGGCUCCAAUGUAAAAUAUCACUACAUCAGUCCACAAGCAACAUUAAGGAAAUCUAAAGGAAAUGGAAUUUGACUUUUUAGAGUAUAAUGAUGUUCUAGGGCAUAAUGAGGAAAAUUUUUAAAAAAUAGAUUAUAAUGAUACAUAUUGGUAUCAUUAAGACAACAGAUUUGAGCAAAUACAAUUAAGGUGUCUUAUUUUUUGCAUCAAGUAAUUAUUGCUGUGGUCUUUCUACUCCACAAAAUAAUUUUUUCUUUUUGCAGUUGAAAAUUAACUGCAUUAUUAACUAAUUAAUAAAAUAAAUCAAGUGGUAUAAGGGAUUAGUUUACCCUCAAGCCGAUGACUCCAUGGCUACUGAUAUUAGUUAGUUUAGGAUUUUUAAAAAGCAUAUCAGACCCCCAGUUUCAGGAAUUGAGUAUAAAUAUUGCUUCUUGUCACCCUGGGACAGUAAUGCCUUAUAGUGGCACUAGUCACCUUAAGUAGAUUACACAUGGUUGAGGUGAAUAAAGCUGCAUGGGAAUUUGCUUUCGUGAUAUAUUUCAUUUGCAAACUUCUACAUAAUCAAGUUUUAUGUUUAAAACCAUCGGUUCUAUAUAUCUAGCUUUAGGAAGUUGCCCUUACAGGUGGGACCUUUUGUGUUAAUCUGUUUUCUCCCCAGUCAUCUUAUUUGGCUAUGUUAAAAAAAAAAAAAAAAAAAAAGCGAGAGAGAGAGAUGGUGUCUCACUGUGUUGCCCAGGCUGGUCUCGAACUCCUGGCCUCAAGUGACUUUCCCACCUCAGCUUCCCAAAGUGCUGGAAUCACAGGCAUGAGCCACAGUGCCUGGUCUUAGCUGUGUUUUUAAUUAUGCCAUGCAUCAACAUAACACCGGGCCAUCUUCCUAUCCCUUCCUAUCCCAUAUGUUUAAUGAAAACAUAUUUUAUGUGCUAAAUUAGGUUAAUUUACCAGAGAUUUAGCUUAGUGUUUUUAAACUAUAGAACAAUACCCCUAUAGAACAAUGUACAGCUGCACCCAAGGUUAAAAAGAGGUAGCAGGGAAAACAAACUUAAACUCUUUGUAUAUGGUGAAACCCAUCCCUCUCCUGCCCUCUAAUGGUAUGUUUACAUUAUUUCGUUAUUAUACAAUGUAGUGGUAUAAACAGUAUUAUUAAACUGAAGGCAUAAGUUAAAGGAAGUAUGUUACUUUGAGCUGAUGUAGGCUCUUCCACUUUUAUCUGUAUUUUACUUAUUUGGGGACUUUGUAUUGCUAGGGCUUCAGAAUACUAACUUUGACACAGCUCCCAGAGAGGUUUGCAAACUUUUGGUUUCCCUCUCAAAUCCAUGGUAGUAGUUUCAAAUGAGUUUGUGGAUAAUGGAUGUUUAGUCCUUAUCAUUUGCUGUGUUUUGACAGUUUUUAAUUUGCAGUAUUCACUCACGAACUGUUUUAUUUUAGGAAUAAUGCAAAACCAACCUUCGUCCGGUGAUGAGAAUAGCCGUAUGAUAAGAGAAUUUGCUCAUCGUGCUUUAAAUGAUUAACUGUUUUACCUUAUUUAGUAUUUCAUAGACUUUGCAUGAUAUGGUACACUCCUAAUUAUGCAUUCUUUGGUUUCCAAAUCUUAAUCUAAGAUACUUUGUUAACUGACUGGUAGCCUAAGAAAGAGACUUUUCUUCCUGUUUUUCUCUCUCCCCAUUUUUUGGGGUAAGUUUUGCAAAGAUCAGUGCUGCUUCUCAUGACUCUAAAGUAAAGCUCUUUUGGAUAGCACAGCCUAACUUUACAGCUAGACAGAAUGGCCAUUAAGAAUAUUUCCAAAAUCCAAGUUUAUCAAAAUUAUUUUGUGGGAAAUCAUCAAUCUAUUUUAUUAAUGUUAUGUGUUUAAUUUUGGACUUAUUUUGGGAAAAACUGUUCAAAUUGGGUCCUUUUAAGCUUAUUUUAAGCAGCCUAGAAGGAAGAAGCUACUUAGCUAAUGAAAGCUGAGACACUUUAUUAAAAGCAGGAUCUUAAGAGCAUUGUUUUUCCUUAAAAACUUUAUACUCUCAGAUAAUCUGCAACAACAAAAAUUAAGAAAUCCCUGACUUUUGUAGAAUUCCCACUGUCAAAUUCUCACUGACUUAUGAGUGUGAGAGAAGUUAUCUUUUGUUUGAAUUCUGAUAGAACAGUUUAACUCCUUUCUAAGGAUAUAAAAAAUUCAUUGGAAAGUGUGUAUAUUUCAAAGACUCUCAAUUAUCUGGACUGAAGGCACUGUUCUCACUAUGGCCAGAUGAAUGGGAGUAUUCUGUACAUGAAUCAUGCUGUAUUUUAAAUCAGGACAUCACUUAAGUAUUAAUGUUGUGUGUACAGAUUUUUGUUUUGGGAUUUUUUUUGCCUAAAUAAAUGUUAUAAAUUUUA